GGGAACUACUCGACCCACAGAGCCGAUCGCGGAGCGGAUUCUGCUUUUAGGAGUACCCGCCAACAAGCGGGACCGAGCAGGAAUCCGUAUCUGGGAACAGGUGAGAGAGGAUGUGUGCUGGGCCUUGGAGGAAGGGGGCCGAGACCGGGCCUUACUUCUGUAACGAUACUGUGAGGCAUCGGAAGGCCAGCCUGUUGUGUCCGUUUUGAAGGAUGCCCCUGUCCCGCUGGUUGAGAUCUGUGGGGGUCUUCCUGCUGCCAGCCCCCUACUGGGCACCCCGGGAGAGGUGGCUGGGUUCCCUACGGCGGCCCUCCCUGGUGCACGGGUACCCAGUCCUGGCCUGGCACAGUGCCCGCUGCUGGUGCCAAGCGUGGACAGAGGAACCUCGAGCCCUUUGCUCCUCCCUCAGAAUGAACGGAGACCAGAAUUCAGAUGUUUAUGCCCAAGAAAAGCAGGAUUUCGUUCAGCACUUCUCCCAGAUCGUUAGGGUGCUGACUGAGGAUGAGAUGGGGCACCCAGAGAUAGGAGAUGCUAUUGCCCGGCUCAAGGAGGUCCUGGAGUACAAUGCCAUUGGAGGCAAGUAUAACCGGGGUUUGACGGUGGUAGUAGCAUUCCGGGAGCUGGUGGAGCCAAGGAAACAGGAUGCUGAUAGUCUCCAGCGGGCCUGGACUGUGGGCUGGUGUGUGGAACUGCUGCAAGCUUUCUUCCUGGUGGCAGAUGACAUCAUGGAUUCAUCCCUUACCCGCCGGGGACAGAUCUGCUGGUAUCAGAAGCCGGGCGUGGGUUUGGAUGCCAUCAAUGAUGCUAACCUCCUGGAAGCAUGUAUCUACCGCCUGCUGAAGCUCUAUUGCCGGGAGCAGCCCUAUUACCUGAACCUGAUCGAGCUCUUCCUGCAGAGUUCCUAUCAGACUGAGAUUGGGCAGACCCUGGACCUCCUCACAGCCCCCCAGGGCAAUGUGGAUCUUGUCAGAUUCACUGAAAAGAGGUACAAAUCUAUUGUCAAGUACAAGACAGCUUUCUACUCCUUCUACCUUCCUAUAGCUGCAGCCAUGUACAUGGCAGGAAUUGAUGGCGAGAAGGAGCACGCCAAUGCCAAGAAGAUCCUGCUGGAGAUGGGGGAGUUCUUUCAGAUUCAGGAUGAUUACCUUGACCUCUUUGGGGACCCCAGUGUGACCGGCAAAAUUGGCACUGACAUCCAGGACAACAAAUGCAGCUGGCUGGUGGUUCAGUGUCUGCAACGGGCCACUCCAGAACAGUACCAGAUCCUGAAGGAAAAUUACGGGCAGAAGGAGGCUGAGAAAGUGGCCCGGGUGAAGGCGCUAUAUGAGGAGCUGGAUCUGCCAGCAGUGUUCUUGCAAUAUGAGGAAGACAGUUACAGCCACAUUAUGGCUCUCAUUGAACAGUACGCAGCACCCCUGCCCCCAGCCGUCUUUCUGGGGCUUGCGCGCAAAAUCUACAAGCGGAGAAAGUGACCUAGAGAUUGCAAGGGCGGGGAGAGGAGGCUCUCAAUAAAUAAUCGUGUAACCUU